GGGGCUUCGCGUCUCCUUCUACGGAUAUCUGUGGACCUUAUGGAAGCAAAGACUCUUGGAACUGUAACGCCCAGAAAACCUGUCUUAUCUGUCAGUGCAAGAAAAAUUAAGGACAAUGCGGCUGAUUGGCACAAUUUAAUCCUGAAGUGGGAAACCCUCAAUGAUGCAGGUUUUACCACUGCAAAUAAUAUUGCCAACUUGAAAAUCAGUUUAUUGAAUAAAGACAAGAUAGAACUAGACAGCAGCAGCCCAGCCUCGAAGGAAAAUGAAGAAAAGGUGUGUCUGGAAUAUAACGAGGAACUGGAGAAGCUGUGUGAGGAACUGCAGGCCACCUUGGAUGGGUUGACCAAAAUACAGGUGAAAAUGGAAAAGCUGUCUUCAACUACCAAGGGAAUUUGUGAACUAGAAAACUACCAUUAUGGGGAGGAGAGUAAACGACCCCCUCUGUUCCACACGUGGCCUACAACCCAUUUCUAUGAGGUUUCGCAUAAGCUCUUGGAGAUGUACAGGAAGGAGCUGCUCCUGAAGCGCACGGUGGCCAAGGAGCUUGCCCACACCGGGGAUCCCGACCUCACCCUGAGCUACCUGUCCAUGUGGCUGCACCAGCCCUAUGUGGAGAGCGACAGCAGGCUGCAUCUGGAGAGCAUGCUGCUGGAGACAGGCCACCGAGCUCUCUGACGUCCUGAGACGGCUGCGGACACUGGCUCCUUCCACGUCUCACCAGGCAGACAGUCUGCCUAGGACCCAGUGCCGCAGGCCUGGAUCAGACCCCAGGAUCAGACCUUGGGGUCUUCUGGCCAGAGCUUGUCACCAGCCCCAUGGCCUCUCCAGGCGUGCUCAUGCCCACAACCCGCGGCCAGCCCCACGUGGUGCUGCUCAGCCUUCUCUGCCCCUCCUGGGAAUCUGUCAUUCGUGGGUGCUUCAGAGUAAAAUCAAUGAGUUUCUGAGCAGAA